ACUGCGCAGGCGCUUACAGUGCACCAAGAUGGCCGCCCCCGUGGAUCUAGAGCUGAAGAAGGCCUUCACAGAGCUUCAAGCCAAAGUUAUUGACACUCAACAGAAGGUGAAGCUCGCAGACAUACAGAUUGAACAGCUAAACAGAACGAAAAAGCAUGCACAUCUUACAGAUACAGAGAUCAUGACUUUGGUAGAUGAGACUAACAUGUAUGAAGGUGUAGGAAGAAUGUUUAUUCUUCAGUCCAAGGAAGCAAUUCACAGUCAGCUGUUAGAGAAGCAGAAAAUAGCAGAAGAAAAAAUUAAAGAACUAGAAGUGGAGGCCAGUUACUGCUUCAACCUAAAGUCAGCCUUCAACCUAAAGUCUGUUAUAUUUUAGGCACAUGCAUAUACAGGUUCACCAGCUUCCUUCCCCUCUGUCUCCAACAUGGUUACCACCCCUUUCACCACCCUGGUUAGCUCAGCAAUAACAGAAUAAGAAUAAGGAAACCUAGGACAGUCUGGCGUGCUUAGCGCCACUUCUGAUGCAGAAUGUUGCAAUCCCAGGGCUGUUGAAAUAACUCCCCAGCCCAUAUCAUAUGUAAAAAAAAAAAACUGUUAAAGUCUUGACGUUUAAAGUCCCAACUCUUCCACAAAAAUGACAGUUUUGGUCAGACAGUGGUUCCUGAAAUAAAUAGGAAGAAUGGCGGCGAGAGAACAGGAUAGGAGGUGCCUGUGACACUCUGCAGUUGGCUUAGGUUUGAUACUCUGAUGAGAACAUGCUUUGGAGGGAUUCCCAUGAUUGAGGAAAUUUUACUCUGCCUGUUGAGAAUCAUUUUUUCCAUCGCAUGGGUGGUGACUGGUAGGCACUUGGAUGGAUGUCCAGUUUUGCCCUAAGUACUGCAUUUUUGAGCUGGUACUAUUGGUGUAUAUAAUAGGAGCCCCCAUUUGGAGGUGAUGUCAGGUGGACUCUACUGUAUGAUAGUCACUGAUUCUUACCUCUGUUUUUCUCUUUUUUUUUUUUUUUUUGAGAUGGAGUCUUGCUCUGUUGCCCAGGCUAGAGUGCAGUGGCACGAUCUCGGCUCACUGCAACCUCCGCCUCCUGGGUUCAAGCGAUUCUUCUGCCUCAACCUCCUGAGUAGCUGGGACUACAGGUGCAUGCCACCAUGCCCGGCUAAUUUUUGUAUCAUUAGUAGAGAUGGGGUUUCACCAUAUUGGCCAGACUUGGUCUUACCUCUGUUUUUCAAUGAAGAAAGGAGGGCAGGGGAUAGCAGAGCCAAUGAUAGAAUGUUUUUAAAACAUUAAACAAGACAUAUGCCCAGCAGUUCAUCUGCUUGCAUAGCUCUAAGUUUAUAAUCCAUUAAAAAUUUAGUCAUUAAUUUUUUAUUGAAAUGUAGCAUUUAAGAAAUGUGUUAAAUAACAUUUAUAGCUUAAUCAUUAUAAAGCAAACACGUCAGUUAUCCAGGCCAGUAAAUCAAAUGUUGUCAGGAAACCAGAACCCUCCUUGUUGUUUAUCACUGCCUAAUCAUGUGCCAUCCCUGCCUGCCUCUCCCAUCAAGUAACUACUUCCCUAACUUUUGUGAUAAUUAUUUCCUUUUUCAAAAAUACAGUUUUACAGCCGGGCAUGGUGGCUCAUGCCUGUAAUCCCAGCACUUUGGGAGGCUGAGGCGGGUAGAUCAUGAGGUCAGGAGUUCAAGACCAGCCUGGCCAAGAUGGUGAAACCCCGUCUCUACUAAAACUACAAAAAUUAGCCGGGCGUGGUGGUGGGCGCCUGUAAUCCUAGCUACUUGGGAGGCUGAGGCCGAGAAUUGCUUGAACCCGGGAGGUGGAGGUUGCAGUGAGCCGAGAUCAUGCCACUGCACUCCAGCCUGGGUGACAGAGCAAGACUCUGUCUCAAAAAAAAAAAAAAAUGGUUUUACCACCUAUGGAUGUAUCUCUAAAAUAAUAUAAUUUAGGCUGGGCGUGGUGGCUCACGCCUGUAAUCCCAGCACUUUGGGAGGCUGAGGCGGGCAGAUCACCUGAGGUCAGGAGUUCAAGGCCAGCCUGGCCAAUAUGGUGAAAUCCUGUCUCUACUAAAAAUACAAAAAUUAGCUGGGCCUGGUGGCACGCGUCUGUAGCCCCAGCUACUCGGGAGGCUGGGGCAGGAGAAUCGCUUGAACCCUGGUGGUGGAGGUUGCAGUGAGCCAAGAUUACGCUAUUGCACUCCGGCCUGGGCGUCACAGUGAGACUCCAUCUCAAAAGACAACAACAAAUAUAUUUUAUGUGUAUAAAUAUAUCUUAUGUAUAUAAAUAUAUAUCUUAUGUAUAUAAAUAUAUAUAUUAUGUAUAUAUGUAUUUUAUGUAUAUAUAUGUGUGUGUAUAUAUAUAAUUUAGUUUAGCUUGUUUCUGAACUUUACAUGAACAAAAUCACUAUUUUUUUGCCUCACUUCUUUCUCUCCACGUUGUGUUUGUGAAGUAUAUCUGUGUUAUCUCUUGAGAUUGUGAGUUGUUCAUUUCAUUGCUGCAUAGUAUCCCGUCAUAUAGAAGUACCACAAUUUAUCUAUCUAGACAGUCCAUUUUUAUUCUUAACAAGUGAAGGUAUUCUCAUGGAGUAUUUUUACAGUUUAUCUUAGCAUCUUGCUAAGAUAAUUUUCAGAAACCACCCUCCACCCACACUCCAGGAGAGCUUGCAUCCUGGGAAGAAGUAUAAAACGUUUACACUCCUGAUGAUUAAAAUUAGCUUGAUGAUUUCCUACUUUCCAUAGUAGCUAGAUAGCUAGACACUUAUGGAUGUCUUUUUAAAAUUUUUAUCUUAGAAAUCAAUGCAAGAUGUAAAAUUAAUCUCUUUCCUACGUUGUUUUGACUUGGAGAGUCUUGGGUGAAGUGAUUUCUCUUAUUGUGCAUAUAUUGGGAUUUCAAACAUGAGUACUUAUCUCUUUAUAGAGCUCAUUUGCAUUCUUAACAUUUAUAAAAAUGUAUGUUUGUUUUAAAAUAGUUUUCGGUUAUUUAGGACUUCAGUCUAAGAGAGCCUGCUGGUUGGAAACCCCAGAGUUUAUCAUGAACUAUAUAUAUAGUCUCUAUGUCCUGAUGUCUUAGGGCUUAAUGUAGCUGCAGAAUCCUCCUUUGUGGCUUUCAGAGAAGAGUUGGUAUAGGUCUGAAAAAGCCCACCAUAUAUGCUCUUUUUCUGUUUGAGCAUUUUUUCUUAUUAAUAUUGUCAAUGCCUUGUUCAUUGUAUAUGUUAUGAUCCAAGUGCUAAAAUUUGCCCAAAUAUAAAGCAUCUGUGAUGCAUUUUAUUUCCUUCAUAGAAGUAUUGUAGAUCCAAUGAGAACUUAGAUGUAAGCAGUUCAAAUAGAUUGGUUCUUUUUUUUUGAGACGGAGUCUUGCUCUGUCACCCAGGCUGGAGUGCAGUGGCGCAAUCUUGGCUCACUGCAAGCUCCACCUCCCAGGUUCACACCAUUCUCCUACCUCAGCCUCCCAAGUAGCUGGGACUACAGGCGCCCGCCACCACGCCCGGCUAAUUUUUUUGUAUUUUUAGAAGAGACAGGGUUUCACCAUGUUAGCCAGGAUGGUCUUGAUCUCCUGACCCCGUUAUCCGCCCGCCUCGGCCUCCCAAAGUGCUGGGAUUACAGGCAUAAGCCAUCGUGCCUGGCCCAUAGAUUGGUUCUUUUAAUUGGAUAGCCUUCCUUAUUUAUCUUGAAAUAUAUAUUACAGAUAUUUAACACACACAUUGAUAUACCCUUGAUUUGAUCUGUUUCCUGGUGGCGCAUCUUCAUUUUAUGAUUAAGAUAAGAGACUUAAGAUAAUUGGAUUUGCAUUCCAAUUAGCCCAGAGUUCAGCUUUUUGCAUCUUGUUUCAGUUAUUAUUUUCUUCUUGGAUACAUUGGGUGCCUUGUUGCUCUCCUUGGAAUACUUAUCUGUCCCCAUACCCAACUAUCCCUUUGAAUGCUUUAGGGAGUUGUUGACCUCAGCCUUCAUUGUUACAUGCUUUAUAUGGUCUAUACUCUUCUCUGUCUAACCAUAUGUCCUUAGUCUCCACCCUCCCAUGCCUGGAUUCCUCAAAUCAUUUUCAGGCUGCCUAGAGAAUGAUUUCUUUUAAUGAGUUAGACUUUGGAUUUUCUUUCAUGUCAUUACAUACUUCCUUGCCAAGAAUCCUUAUCCUAGAUUCUUACUCUGAUCAGUUUCUGUUCUUACAUCACAGGUGUCCUCCAACCUGAGGUAAUAGAUACUAGCCAUAAAAAGCAAGUUCAAUACUUCAUGUGGGGAAGGCCACACCUUUAUUAAUAAGCAUGCUACACAUCAGCUCAGAAAAAGAUCCAAAGAAAGGUUGACAUUUCAGCCAUAAAUAGAAAUUUCCAAGUCUACUAGAUUUACAACAGAGCGUUCAUUACCCUAAAUUCCUAAUUUUAAAAGCCUUAUGUUAAUUUAGGAGUUCUUCAUUCUAACUCUUGCUGUACGCUAAGCCUCAGUUUCCUCACAUAAAAUGAGAAUAUUGGAUUAGAAGAUCUCUAGGGUCACUCCAGUCACUUCUAUUAAGUUUAUUGUUAUAACCUUGGUCUUUUUCUGAGUUUCCAUUUUAGGAGCAAAAAUGCCCCCUUAAAAUGAAAAGAUGGAGGAAAGCAAAACAAA